ACAGACGCAAGCCCAGUGCCACAGGCCGCGGGGGCGGGGAGGACGGCGCCCGGGGACAGAGAACAUGGGACGCAGAGCGGUCCAAGGCCCCGGCGCCCUGGUGAGGCCCAAACCUCCCGCCAUGCCCCGGCCCCAACGAGACCCAAGCCCCCUGUCCCGGCCCAGCGCCCGCGGGGGACCCAAGCCCCAGCCUGGUCCACCUCGGAGGCCUCUAGGACCCGGGGGCGCCCGGCGGCCCGCCCGGCUCCCACAAAUAGACUCCUGGGCGGGCGCCUGAGCCCCCAAAAUAGAUCCUCAGGGCCCAAAAGCAGACUCUUCGGCGGGCGCCAUGGGACCGGCAGAAGCUGGGCGCCGCGGGGCCGCCUCGCCCGUACCUCCACCGUUGGUGCGCGUCGCGCCCUCACUCUUCCUCGGGAGCGCGCGAGCCGCGGGCGCGGAGGAGCAGCUGGCGCGCGCGGGAGUCACGCUGUGCGUCAACGUCUCCCGCCAGCAGCCCGGCCCGCGCGCGCCCGGCGUGGCAGAGCUGCGCGUGCCCGUGUUCGACGACCCGGCUGAGGACCUGCUGGCGCACCUGGAGCCCACGUGCGCCGCCAUGGAGGCCGCGGUGCGCGCCGGCGGCGCCUGCCUAGUCUACUGCAAGAACGGCCGCAGCCGCUCGGCCGCCGUCUGCACCGCGUACCUCAUGCGGCACCGCGGCCUCAGCCUGGCGAAGGCCUUCCAGAUGGUGAAGAGCGCUCGCCCGGUAGCAGAACCGAACCCGGGCUUCUGGUCUCAGCUCCAGAAGUAUGAGGAGGCCCUCCAGGCCCAGUCCUGCCUGCAGGGAGAGCCCCCAGCCUUAGGGUUGGGCCCUGAGGCUUGAAGCUUGAAGGCCUGCUGCCUGGAGGAAGGAUGUCCCUGCACUGAUACAGAAGGCUGGUCUUUACCCUUCUUCCUCACUGUCAUAUCGAGUUUUCCUUUGUGUGUGUGUGUGUGAAACAUAGUGCUUUUAAUUUUAUAUUUCCGGCUGAGGUGAUGCACAAAUUAUCUUACAGACACAAAAAGAAAUACAUUUGGUAAAACAUCGAAGACAAAUUAAGAAAAAGCAAAUAGGGAUCCUCCAUUAUUUACACUCCAGAAUCUUGAGUGUUUGGGGGUGCCGGCGCAUUCUACCAGUCUCAGGGAAGGACAUGAGUACAGACUACAGUAAUCAGAAUCUGAGUCAUAGGUGAAAUCAGGAAAAGCAACUCUUCUUGUGUUUAUUUUUAGUAGUGUCAUAAGAACGGACUAGUUCUUCCUGCGUGACCACGGAUGCUUCUGUUUGAGAAAAUGCAUACCCACGUGGGACAUUUAGAUCAAGAAAGCUGUUGAUGAAGACAUUGUUGAAGGGCAACUUGGGUGAUUGGGGAAUUAUUCUCUUCAUCAGCCCCUCUGCAAUACAGCUGGAGCUGUCCCAUAGGAGUUCGGACAAUUACGGACAUCCUUUUUCUUUCUCUCUUUCUUUUUUUUUGUUUGUUUGUUUGAGACAGAGUCUCUGUUGCCCAGGCUGGAGUGCAGUGGCGCAAUCCCGGCUCACUGCAACCUCCGCCUCCCUGGUUCAAGUGAUUCUCCUGCCUCAGCCUCCUGAGUAGCUGGGACUACAGGUGUGUGACACCAGACCCGGCUAAUUUUUUGUAUUUUUAGUAGAGAUGGGGGGUUUCACCAUGUUAGCCAGGAUGGUCUCAAACUCCUGACCUCGUGAUCCACCCACCUCAGCCUCCCAAAGUGCUGGGAUUACAGGCGUGAGCCACCGUGCCCAGCCUCCUUUUUCUAUUACUAGAGAACUCCAGGACAUUAAGAAUUUCAAAAGUGAUUUUUUCACCCAUGGCUUCUACGGUGACAGAGUAUGGUGUUCCUGUAGGGAAACAAAGCCAAGUUUUUUUGCUCCUUUCACUAAAGCUGCUUCAUCCGGGGAGGAAGCCUGGUAGAUUAUAAUAUUUCCAGGGAUAACAGUGUGGCACACAGAUAACAGGGUAAGAAAUUGGUCUAUAUAGUUUUCUGUGGGAUGGCCAUUCUCAAUGUUCUCCAAUAAACUGGGGUAAUUAAAAUAUCAGGGCUCGGAUGGAAGGUGUUGCACCAUAAAUGACACCUGCAGUGGUACUUGUUAAAUGUCUUAACAUUGCAAGUGAGGGUUCCCAUUUUAUCAGAAAAUAGAAAUUUUACCUGCCCAAGUUCUUCACUGAGAUUGAAUGUGCUGGCCAUGGUGUGGACACUAUUUACUUUAUAAUGCACAUCUUGAUCCCAGUUUAUAAACUGGGCCUGAAUAUAUUUCACAAUUUCCAUAGUGACCAGCAGACUAAUGGGGAUGAGGUACUGUUAUAAGAUGAUGAACACCAGUAUGUCAAACACAAUGCUGUGAGCUGGAAUCCUCUUUCAGGUACCAAAUGUCACCAUACUUUUUAUUCCAUAGCACGGCUCCCACGCAGCUCACUACAGACAUGACCAGAGCAGCAGGAACCAAAGGGAGACCCGCCCAUUGUCACUUUCUUAAUCUCUGAUCUCUUGAGGUGAUUUGACAGAAUUCUGCAGGAAUUUGGUUUCAAAGCCAGUGUAAACAACUAUGCCAGUGAUCCACUGAGCAUUUCUUUUUUUUUUUUCUUGAGACGGAGUCUCACUCUGGUGCCCAGGCUGGAGUGGGCGCCAUCUUGGCUCACUGCAAGCUCCGCCUCCCGGCUUCAUGCCAUUCUCGUCCUUCAGCCUCCUGAGUGGCUGGGAUUACAGGCGCCCGCCACCACGCCUAGCUAAUUUCUUUGUAUUUUUGGUAGAGACGGGGUUUCACUGUGUUAGCCAGGAUGGUCUCAAUCUCCUGACCUCAUGAUCCUCCCGCCUCGGCCUCCCAAAGCGCUGGGAUUACAGGCGUGAGCCACCUCGCCCGGCCAAUCCACUGAGCAUUUCUAAGCUGUGUAUCUCUUAACAAGACCCAGUCAGGCCCUAUUGGAACAGGGCUUUUACCACCUAGGCGGAAGCUCAGCCAUUGAAAUGACGAUCAGGUGCUUCACGGUCUAUUUUUCCAGAUAGGCCUAACAGCUGGUUUUCUGUUUGCAUUUCAGCUGUUUCUGGCAAAGCCUGCCGUGUCUUACAUUUGUCUCUCUAUCCGGAUUAGAUGUUGCUAUAUGAACACAUCGGGACUGUGUCUGCAGGAAGGAGCUCCCCAUUCGAGGCCUUCACAGUGUCACCCACAUUCACCUCUUUCCACUUAAACGUGUCCCAUGAAUCUUGUCAUAACAGUUUUGUGUUCCUUAACUAUUUUGUCUGCCAUGUCAUUUAUGAUGUAUAUAACCUCUUUAAUGCCUGAAAUCAUAAGAAUAAUCAUCAAAGGCAAGAGGGUUGUAUAUUUUCCCGUUGGAGACACAUCUGGAAUUUGCUGCAAUAAAAUAAUAAUAAGAAAGCAUUGGCAGCUUUGGUAAACUGCAGAUUCAAAAAUCGAGGGAGAAAUGAGCACACGCUGUACUUGGCUGUACAUAUAAUUGCUGACUGUGGGUUGCAGAAAUUUCUCUCAAGCAUCAUCACCACUUUUGCUCAGUUAUCAGUAGUAAUAACAGCAAUCAAAACUGAAACUGCUCCAGAUGCCUGUCUAGGAAGUAUGGUUUUCCAUCCUUCCUACUGCUUUCUUCACAAGAGAAUCCUCCACCUCAGUGGCCCUGAAGUGGCCUGAAGGGCCCGCUCUGCGGUCCUGCCACCAGUGCCCUCUGAGGUCCAUGGUCCCACGGCACCACGGCCGCCCAGUGCACUCGCCUCCACACUGAGUUUUCAUUUUUCCCAGUUAAGCCCCAUCUUCCGGAAAUGCAGCUCCAGAGGGUCUCUGUCCCCUCUUGCUGGUGGGGCAAGGGUCUGCGCAUCAGACCACAUGGACCCCUGCACCACCAUCUGCUCCGUCCUCUCCCUCUGGUCAGCUCAGCUUAUUAAACAAGCCUUGGUCAGGAAAAUCUAAACCACUUAAGGAACUGGGCAGAAAGAAACUGAAUGCAGGGAGAAGAAGGCUGGGGAGCCAAGGACAGGAGAGGAGACAUAGGGGAGUCACAGGGACCUGCCACCCAGAUCCCCACUGCCUGAUGUCCUGGCUGUGGAGGGCACCUGGAGCUGCCAGCAGAGCCUCCUGCCCACCAGCUGCUGAAGCCACAGUACAUCUCCUUCCUCCCACCUCCCAGACCUCUCACUGGUCUCAUCUGGGCACCGAACAUGGGAAGCCCCUCCUGUGACAGGCAGGGGAGAAGGAGGCUGUGCUGACAGACGGCCUGGUGAGGGAACCCGGGAGGCCUCCAGCAUCUGCACCCCUCUCCUACUUUGAUCUCUGUUUCACCAACAUUGCACCCCAACUUAAGGUCACAUAGCUACUGUCAAGCCAACAAGGUGCUGCCUCUCCCGCCGUGUGAGGGUGGAACCCCAUAAGCCACCACUGGAGGCAUCCAAGCAUGUUGAUUCCUUCUCUAGUUCAGACACCACCUCUCCUGGACAUCCUGUGGCCUAAAGACUAUCCUAGAAUCAACACUCCUUAAAUAGGAGUGGGGAAAGAAAAGGAAAAUGUGUGUAAUACAUGUGAAUCACAGAUAACGUAGUCAUUGGUUAAUAUAUACAACUACGCGUAUUUACAUUCUGUAUGCGUCAAUGAGUAAAAUACUGUGGUUGGUGCUUA